GGCCGCGGGCUGGGCCCCGCCGCAGCUCCAGCUGGCCGGCUUGGUCCUGCGGUCCCUUCUCUGGGAGGCCCGACCCCGGCCGCGCCCAGCCCCCACCAUGCCACCCGCGGGGCUCCGCCGGGCCGCGCCGCUCACCGCAAUCGCUCUGUUGGUGCUGGGGGCUCCCCUGGUGCUGGCCGGCGAGGACUGCCUGUGGUACCUGGACCGGAAUGGCUCCUGGCAUCCGGGGUUUAACUGCGAGUUCUUCACCUUCUGCUGCGGGACCUGCUACCAUCGGUACUGCUGCAGGGACCUGACCUUGCUUAUCACCGAGAGGCAGCAGAAGCACUGCCUGGCCUUCAGCCCCAAGACCAUAGCAGGCAUCGCCUCAGCUGUGAUCCUCUUUGUUGCUGUGGUUGCCACCACCAUCUGCUGCUUCCUCUGUUCCUGUUGCUACCUGUACCGCCGGCGCCAGCAGCUCCAGAGCCCAUUUGAAGGCCAGGAGAUUCCAAUGACAGGCAUCCCAGUGCAGCCAGUAUACCCAUACCCCCAGGACCCCAAAGCUGGCCCUGCACCCCCACAGCCUGGCUUCAUAUACCCACCUAGUGGUCCUGCUCCCCAAUAUCCACUCUACCCAGCUGGGCCCCCAGUCUACAACCCUGCAGCUCCUCCUCCCUAUAUGCCACCACAGCCCUCUUACCCGGGAGCCUGAGGAACCAGCCAUGUCUCUGCUGCCCCUUCAGUGAUGCCAACCUUGGGAGAUGCCCUCAUCCUGUACCUGCAUCUGGUCCUGGGGGUGGCAGGAGUCCUCCAGCCACCAGGCCCCAGACCAAGCCAAGCCCUGGGCCCUACUGGGGACAGAGCCCCAGGGAAGUGGAACAGGAGCUGAACUAGAACUAUGAGGGGUUGGGGGGAGGGCUUGGAAUUAUGGGCUAUUUUUACUGGGGGCAAGGGAGGGAGAUGACAGCCUGGGUCACAGUGCCUGUUUUCAAAUAGUCCCUCUGCUCCCAAGAUCCCAGCCAGGAAGGCUGGGGCCCUACUGUUUGUCCCCUCUGGGCUGGGGUGGGGGGAGGGAGGAGGUUCCGUCAGCAGCUGGCAGUAGCCCUCCUCUCUGGCUGCCCCACUGGCCACAUCUCUGGCCUGCUAGAUUAAAGCUGUAAAGACAUAACUCAUAUCAGUCGCAUCAUUGGACCCAUCCACACCUUCCAGGAACACCGCCUUCAGCUGGGCCCAGACUGUUGCCCACUCCAUAUUCCAAAAGUAGGGGAGGGCCAGCACCAGCAUCGGAGCACAGCACCAUCCUCACCCCCAUCCACAAGCAGACCAAGGCGGACUGUUCCUGGCUUCCUAAAGGCUUCCUAAAGACAAUGAGGUGAAUUUUGCCACAGCUCUGAAGAGAUGCUCGUUUGCACUACAGAUAUUCCCUGCUAGGGAUCAACAGCUCUACAACAGC